GGUGGGGAGGGGUGGCCCCGGAGGGCUCCCGGGGGCAGAGGGCCUCGUUCUCAGGGUGCCCCCUCCUUGGCAGAGGUGCUUGCAGAGAAGUGGGUCCCUGCUCCUUCCAGUUGUGGCAGCUCUCUUCCCCAGGGUGCAGGAGCUGAGCAGGUCUGAGACCCCGGCCUCGGCCUGGCUGGUUGGUGGUGGGGAUGGGGGCUAGUGCGCCCAAUCCCGGCGGCCCUGUGUUUCUCACAGGCUGUGCUGCUCCACGCAGAGAAGCUGUUCCUGAAGCUUCUUUUUGGGCUGGGGUCGCUGGCGGCUGCAGGCUCUGGGCAUAUUGCCUGCUGCCCACGGUUUCAAAGCUGCCAGCACUCGCUGGGCUCCGCCUGCUGCCCCCCCGGGGGUCACAGGCCACAUGGCUUGGUGGCCGAACUCCACGUGCUGGCUCCUCACAGCUGUCACCAUGGCCUUGGCUACCCGCUGCGUCCCUCAGGAGCUGCCAUCAGGUUCUGAGGUGCCUGGUCUGGAGGCAGUCCAGGUGGUGAGGUCUGGACUGGCUGGACCCCACCGAUGCUCCUGCCGUCACCCCGUCCUGGCCCUCACUGGAGGCAGGGACACUCAGGGGCCCGGGGCCUCGGGGCCAGUGCUGCAGUGGCCGCCGUUGCUCUCACAGCGGGUCCAGGCCUGGCUUCUGAAGGCAAUGUGCCUGCGUCUCACACUCAAAAGGGCCUGCCAGGCUGCACCUGGCGGCAGCUCCCACGGGGGACGAUGUCCUGCUGUCUGUUGGCCCCCAGGUGGGAGGGACGGGCGUGGAGCUGCAGGCAGUGGGCAAGGCCAUGGCAGGUGGCCAGGCCUGGGAACCAGCCUCCAGGUGGCAUCCACGCUGAGGCCUGAGCUCCGGCCGACAAGGACUGGGGAUGCAGGGGAUUAGCCAGGGGCUGUGUGGGGGAGCCCUGGAGCCCUGUCUGCGAGUUACCCCGAUGAACAGGGAGACGCGGCAGAGGCAGGGCCGGGGAGGGGCCGUGUGGGGGAGCCCUGGAGCCCUGUCUGCGAGUUACCCUGAUGGACAGAGAGACGCGGCAAAGGCAGGGCCGGGGAGGGGCCGUGUGGGGCCUGGUGGUCGGCAGAGGAAGGGUCUGUGCUCCUCCUGCGUGUGGUGGCACCGGAGCGCCUCCCAGUUCCUGGUGUUACCGCACCAGCCGCCUCCCAGUGAGCAUCUCCACGUGUGCCGACAACAGCUUUGUUGAGGUAGAACUUACCAGACUCACCUGUUAAAAGAGUGCAGUUUGGUCACUCUUAGUGGUUUGUAGAGUUGUGCAGCCGUCAUUGCAAUCCAGCGUUGCAGCAUUCCACAGCCCACAGGGACCCCCAGCCCCACAGUCCAGUGUUACAGCAUCCCGCAGCCCAGAGGGACCCUCAGCCCCAGACGGCCACUGACCGGCUUCCUGUCUUGGUUUGCCUUGUGCAGAAGGUGCGUGGAUGUGGGGCCACAGGACGUGGCUGGCUGGGUUUGCCUUGUGCAGAAGGUGCGUGGAUGUGGGGCCACAGGACGUGGCUGGCUGGGUUUGCCUUGUGCAGAAGGUGCGUGGAUGUGGGGCCACAGGACGUGGCUGGCUGGGUUUGCCUUGUGCAGAAGGUGCGUGGACGUGGGGCCACAGGACGUGGGGCCCCGUGUCUGGCCUCUUCACUCGGCACCGUGCCCUCCAGAUUCAUGCACCUGCAGCCCGAGGCAGUUUCAUUCACUGCUCCUUUGCGGGAUGAACCGCAUUUUAUCUAUUCAUGGACGCUAGGACUGCUUCCACGUGGCUUCUGUGGACAAUGCUGUGAACAUUGUUUACGAGGUUUUGCGUGGACCUGUUUUCAUUUAUCUUGCAUAGAUACCUAGGAGUGGGAUUGCUGGGGCGUGUGGUGAACUUUCAUAAUGUCUUGAGGAACUGCCAAGCCAUCUUCCGCAGCGGCUGCAUUACCUAGUUCCCACCGGCAACGCUGGGGAGGGUCCUGGCGUCUCCACUCCCUCGACAGCUCCUGCCGUUGUCUGUCCUUGUGAUUCUGGCCGUCCCAGGGGGUGGGAGCUGGUGUCCCCUUGGCUUUGAUCUGCGUUUCCCUGGUGGCCAGCCAUGUGGGGCCUCUCUCCCUGUCUCAUCCACCCGUGCCUGUCUUUUUUUCAUUCAUUCACUUAUUUAUUUAUUUAGAGACAGGGUCUUACUCUGUCACCCAGGCUGGAGUACAGUGGUGUGAUCACAGCUCACUGCAGCUUCUACUUCCUGGGUUCAAGAGAACCUCCCAUCUCAGCCUCCCAAGUAGCUGGAACUACAGGCGUGCACCACCAUAGCUGGUUAAUUAGAAAAAAAAAAUUUGGCCAGGCGCAGUAGCUCACGCCUGUAAUCCCAGCACUUUGGGAGGCCGAGGCGGGUAGAUCACCUGAGGUCAGGAGUUCAAGACCAGCCUGGCCAACAUGGUGAAACCCCAUCUCUACUAAAACAAAAAUUAGCUGGGCGUGGUGACGGGCACCUAUAAUCCUAGCUACUAGGGAGGCUGAAGCAGGAGAAUCGCUUGAACUUGGGAGGCGGAGGUUGCAGUGAGCCAAGAUUGCACCACUGCACUCCAGUGUGGGCGACAGAGUGAGACUCUGUCUCAAAAUAAAAAUACAAACCCUGAGCUUGGGAGGGUCCAGGCUGCAAUGAGCUGCGAUCGUGCCACCGCACUCCAGCUUGGGCGACACAGUGAGACGCUAGACGGUGUCUCAAAAAACUUAAACAGAAAAAUGUAGAAAGGAUUGUCGUUCCCUUUCUCGUUUUCCAGAGGGCAGAGGACUCUCGGCCCCUGCUUUUUGAGCACCAGGCCGAGUUUCAGACCUCGGGAUGGCCUCUCCAGUCUGCAGCUCCCGGCAGCCUCGGGCCACACUCCCGGGAUCCCCAGGGACUGGCCUGGGACUACCGGGGGUGGCGGCCGUGGCUCUGGCUAUGGGGAGGGAGGCAGAGCCGCGGGGCAGGCGUGGGGUCUGCUGUGCCGGGUAUGUGGGGCGUGUGUUAGACUUUGGACCUGGCCUGCGGGGUCAGGCCGUGGUGUAUGAUGACGCCACGCCGCUCUUUCUCUUUCACCCUGGCCUCCUGCCUGGCCCUCCCCUGGGUCGGCAUCCCUGGGGCCACUCCUGCCCGUGCCCGCUGCUGUGGGGCCUGGGCUCCAGGCAGCUCCUGUCUGCUGCUGCAAACAGGCCCCCAAGGUGCAUGGUGAGGAGACCCCCAGGCUAGAGAUGGGCGAGAGCGGUGGGCGAGCAGACUGCGGGAAGGCAGCUGGGCCUCCACACGCGGAGCCCUCCCCACCACGUGCAUGCACAGGCGACCCCUGCCGUGCUCCGACGGAGGGCGCCGGGACUGGGGAGGGUCAGCGCGACAGCCCUGGCGUUUACUGAAGAGCUGCCUGCCUGGCUCGCUGCCCUGGUGGCCGCUGAAUUCUCCCAACGCCCCAGGACAGCAGGUGCUGUGGCCCCAUGACCGCUCCCCCACAUGGAUGAAGGGGUGGUGCACAGGCUGGUGGAGCCUGGGAGAGCCAGGGCAGCCUGCGGCCAUGCGGCCAUGCGGCCGGCGUGGGGCUGAGGUCCCUGUACAGCUGACAGAGUGCCUGGCGCCCUCAAUCAGUAAGUCAUCUACGGGCCGGGCACCGGCGGCUCAGCACAGAGAGGCAACAAGGGUAGACCCCCCCUGGCAAGGCUGACCGGCGCCGGGCUGUGGCCAGACCAGGAGACUGCAGCCCAGCUCGAGGGAGGCACCACGCCUGCCCCUCAGAGCACUGAGCAGAGCCCCCCAUGGUAUCCCCCGCCCUGGGCACAGCAGGAGGAGCUGCCGACCAAGUCUGGCACCCCGGUGUGCCCCGAGAGCUGUCUGGGCACAGGUUGCGGGGCUGCCCCGGCCGGACGGGGCAUCUGUGUUUCUCGGUGUGGCCUCAGGGCUCUGGUGGCUUUGACCGAGGCCCCGGGGGACAGAAUGCAGCUUCCUGCUCCUCACUUUUCCUAAGAAAGGGGCCGCCUCCCAGGACUGGGGCUGCGCCAGUCACAGGCCCGCGGCCUCCACGCUCCGGGUGCUGCUGUCCCGGCUGCUUCAGGGCGGGCUCUGUCUUGCACGCAGCGAGCGGCUUCAUCACCUCCCUUUUGAAUUGGAGCUGAGUGUCGGCAACGCCCAGAUAACUGGGGCGCGCGGGUCUUUUGUGCUGGAUUUUUCUGUACAGUUGCCUCGAUCUUCCAUCCAGCUUGGCCUCUGUGCAGUAAGGAGCGGCCCGUCGCCUCCCCCACGUCGCCUCCCCCACGUCGCCUCCCCCACGUCGCCUCCCCCACGUCGUCGCCUCCCCCACGUCGCCUCCCCCACGUCGUCUCCCCCACGUCGUCGUCUCCCCCACGUCGCCUCCCCCACGUCGCCUCCCCCACGUCGCCUCCCCCACGUCGCCUCCCCCACGUCGCCUCCCCUCACGUCGUCGUCUCCCCCCACGUCGUCGUCUCCCCUCACGUCGUCUGCCCUGAGCCCGCUCCCUUCGAAGGUAACCAUCCUGCAGUAGUGAGGGCUCCUUGCUGAGCACGUGUGGCUGCGACUUCAGGAGCGUUCUGGGUUGAGAAUUCCAAAAGGGCUUCGCUCAGGCCUGGCUUUGGGUCUUUGGGCUCCUGACGCGAGCUUUUACUUCCAGGCUUUGGCGGUCUGGCCUCAGGAGGUCAAGGCUGCAGUGAGCCGUGCGCGAGCCACUGCACCAUCCUGGGCAAUCAGACCCCAUCUCUAAAGUUCAAAACAACAUCUUUGUAAGGGUUUCGGGUCUCUGAGCCCAUGAACCUGCCCAGGCCCUGCAGAGGUGAGGGUGGCCCUAGAGUGGCUGGGGGGUUGUGGAGACCAGAACCAGGGCAGAAGGGCAGGGAGGGUGGGGGCCCUGCCGAGGUCUCCCACCGCUGACCCCUGACCCCUGGCCCCCUUCCACCUCGGCCCACCGAGAGAGGCCGGCACAGCGCAGACUGCGGGGUCAGUGACACUCCCCUCAGCGUCUCCAGCCACAGAAGGGCCGUGGCCUGCCUUCGCCCUCCUCACCCGUGUCCCGGGGCCACGUUUGAACUUUAGGCCUUGUUCUGACUUCAUUGAAACCCUCCUGAAGUGCAGACGUCUUCCUGACCCACCUGGGUUUUGCCAGGAUGACUCCGAAAGGUGUCUCCCAGCAGACACACCCCGCUGGCGAUUGUUUGGUCCUGGGGACCCGGGUUCUCAUUCUCCUCUCUGGAGCUGGUGAGGCUGUCCUUGCUAGUCGGUGACAACUACAGGGCCAAAGGGAGGGUGUGUCCCAGGAGGCCCAGCCCACCUCUGCCUGCACCUGCGGUCAGCGGGGUGCAGAGUCUGUGAAGGCACCUCCCGGAGUGGGGGCUGCAAAGAUCAUGGCCACUGUGCCACCCACAGGGGCCCAGGCCGGACGCCUGGGCUGUGCCGCCUCGGCAGCCAGGCCGAGGAACGUGCAGGUGCGGCCGGGAGCCCGCCGGCCACAGCUGCAUCCAUGCCCUUCUCCGAGUGGUGAUGGCGGGGAGAGGCCUGGCUGUCUACGGGCAGAUUGCUUGGGCUUUCACAGAAGCCCGCUGUUAGAGCAGAUUCCCGGCCUUGGGUCUCUCUGCUCCAGCUGGACGCCCUGAGCCUCGCCGGGCCCAGUCCACCCCCGUCCACUCUGCCAGGGGCAGCUCAGAGCCCUCGCCACGCGGGGCUGAGCGCAGGGAAGGCAGCAUCACGGAGUUCGCUCGGCUCCACAGAACACCCGUGUUGCUCGCGGAGACUUUUUGUUUUUGUGCUUCUUAUGAAGAGGCAGGUUUUCUUUCUUCCUGAACCAAAAGGGUUUAGAUGGAGCACAAGAUUCAGGCCAUAUUUACAAGAACAAUUGAUUUUUCUGCCAGGCAGAGCAGCCAGUCUGUCUCGGAGGCUGUGCUGUGGUGUGGGGAGGCCCCUUGCUCAGAUCAGCCUGUGCCUUCCCCAGGCCCCGGCCCAUGCACCUGCCCUUCCGUAGGUCUGAGCACCUGUUCUUCCACGCCCAGGACGACCUGGUCCUGAGUUUGGCCGGGACCCCCUGCUAUCUGCCGUCCACAGGCCUGGUGACAGAGAAAGCAGUGCCCUGGAACAGCAGCCCGGCUGUGGGGUGCUCAGCCCUCUCUGUAGGAUCCUGUGUGGCUCAAGGGGUCUGCUGAGCCUCCAACGGGCAAGAGGGGCCCUGAGCCAUGGAUCCAUUCUGGGUGGAGGCAGCCCCCACCGCCGCCUGCCUCAAAUGCUCAGCCCUAGGCCCUCGGCCCCGUAGCUCUGCAGCCACAGACGGGUGCCUUCCCCAGGCCGAGAGGAGGGUGGGGUCCAGCCACUCAGGACCUCACAGGGUGGCCCUGAUGAGCACCUUCCCUUGCAGCCACACCCACUCGCCCGGGUCUAUGGCCACGGUCGGAGAGUGGUCCUGUGUGCGCUGCACCUUCCUGAACCCGGCCGGCCAGCGCCAGUGCUCCAUCUGCGAGGCUCCCCGGCACAAGCCCGACCUCAACCACAUCCUGCGGCUCAGCGUGGAGGAGCAGAAAUGGCCCUGCGCCCGCUGCACCUUCCGCAACUUCCUGGGCAAGGAGGCCUGCGAGGUGUGCGGCUUCACCCCGGAGCCUGCGCCUGGGGCUGCCUUCCUGCCAGUCCUCAACGGGGUCCUCCCCAAGCCACCCGCCAUCCUGGGGGAGCCCAAGGGCAGCUGCCAGGAGGAAGCAGGUCCAGUGAGGACUGCGGGGCUGGUGGCCACGGAGCCCGCCAGGGGGCAGUGCGAGGACAAGGACGAGGAGGAGAAGGAGGAGCAGGAGGAGGAGGAGGGAGCGGCGGAGCCCAGAGGGGGCUGGGCGUGUCCGCGUUGCACGCUGCACAACACGCCCGUGGCCAGCUCCUGCUCCGUCUGCGGGGGCCCACGCAGGCUCUCGCUGCCACGGAUCCCUCCUGAGGCCCUGGUGGUCCCGGAAGUGGUGGCCCCGGCCGGCUUCCACGUCGUGCCUGCCGCGCCUCCACCUGGCCUCCCCGGGGAAGGUGCCGAGGCCAACCCCCCAGCCACCAGCCAGGGCCCAGCUGCCGAACCAGAGCCGCCCAGGGUCCCGCCCUUCAGCCCCUUCUCGUCCACCCUGCAGAACAACCCCGUGCCGCGCAGCCGACGCGAGGUUCCCCCCCAGCUGCAGCCACCGGUGCCUGAGGCUGCCCAGCCGUCACCCUCUGCCGGCUGCAGGGGAGCCCCCCAGGGCUCGGGCUGGGCUGGGGCCUCCCGCCUAGCAGAGUUGCUGUCUGGCAAGCGGCUGAGUGUGCUGGAGGAAGAGGCCACGGAGGGUGGCACCAGCCGCGUAGAGGCCGGCAGCUCCACCUCGGGCAGUGACAUCAUUGACCUGGCCGGAGACACCGUGCGUUACACGCCCGCCAGCCCCUCCAGCCCCGACUUCACCACCUGGUCAUGUGCCAAGUGCACGCUCAGAAACCCCACAGUGGCCCCCAGGUGCUCGGCCUGCGGCUGCUCCAAACUGCACGGCUUCCAGGAGCAUGGCGAGCCCCCCACCCACUGCCCCGACUGUGGGGCCGACAAGCCCAGCCCCUGCGGCAGAAGCUGCGGACGGGUGUCCUCGGCCCAGAAGGCCGCCCGCGUCCUGCCCGAGCGCCCGGGCCAGUGGGCCUGCCCUGCCUGUACCCUGCUCAACGCACUGCGGGCCAAGCACUGCGCCGCCUGCCACACGCCUCAGCUCCUGGUGGCCCAGCGGCGGGGGGCCGCGCCCCUGAGGCGCAGGGAGAGCAUGCACGUGGAGCAGCGGCGGCAGACAGACGAGGGCGAGGCCAAGGCACUCUGGGAGAACAUCGUGGCCUUCUGCCGGGAGAACAAUGUGAGCUUCGUGGAUGACAGCUUCCCUCCCGGGCCCGAGUCUGUCGGCUUCCCCGCGGGUGACAGCGUGCAGCAGCGUGUGAGGCAGUGGCUGCGACCCCAGGAGAUCAACUGCUCCGUCUUCAGGGACCACAGGGCCACGUGGUCUGUGUUCCACACACUGCGGCCCUCAGACAUCCUGCAGGGGCUGCUGGGGAACUGCUGGUUCCUGAGCGCCCUGGCGGUGCUGGCGGAGCGGCCGGACCUGGUGGAGCGGGUGAUGGUCACGCGCAGCCUGUGUGCAGAGGGCGCCUACCAGGUGCGGCUGUGCAAGGACGGCACGUGGACCACGGUGCUGGUGGACGACAUGCUGCCCUGUGAUGAGGCCGGCUGCCUCCUCUUCUCACAGGCGCAGCGGAAGCAGCUGUGGGUGGCCCUCAUCGAGAAGGCGCUGGCCAAGCUGCACGGCUCCUACUUUGCGCUCCAGGCGGGCCGCGCCAUCGAAGGCCUGGCCACGCUCACCGGCGCCCCCUGUGAGAGCCUGGCGCUGCAGCUCAGCUCCACUAACCCCCGCGAGGAGCCCGUUGACACUGACCUCAUCUGGGCCAAAAUGCUGAGUUCUAAGGAGGCUGGGUUCCUCAUGGGUGCCUCCUGUGGCGGGGGCAACAUGAAGGUGGACGAUUCGGCCUACGAGAGCCUGGGCCUGCGCCCCCGGCAUGCCUACUCCAUCCUGGAUGUCCGAGAUGUCCAGGGCACCAGGCUUCUGCGGCUCCGAAACCCGUGGGGCCGUUUCUCCUGGAACGGCAGCUGGUCCGACGAGUGGCCACACUGGCCGGGGCACCUGCGUGGCGAGCUCAUGCCGCACGGCAGCAGUGAGGGUGUCUUCUGGAUGGAGUACGGCGACUUUGUCAGGUACUUCGACUCCGUGGACAUCUGUAAGGUGCACUCGGACUGGCAGGAGGCGCGGGUGCAGGGCUGCUUUCCCAGCUCGGCCAGCGCGCCCGUGGGGGUAACAGCGCUCACGGUGCUGGAGCGGGCCUCGCUGGAGUUCGCGCUCUUCCAGGAGGGCAGCAGGCGCUCGGACGCCGUGGACAGCCACCUGCUGGACCUGUGCAUCCUGGUGUUCCGGGCCACGUUCGGCAGCGGCGGCCACCUCAGCCUGGGCCGCCUCCUGGCCCACAGUAAGCGCGCGGUCAAGAAGUUCGUCAGCUGCGACGUCAUGCUGGAGCCUGGCGAGUACGCUGUGGUGUGCUGCGCCUUCAACCACUGGGGGCCGCCCCUGCCGGGCACCCCUGCCCCCCAGGCCUCCAGCCCCUCGGCAGGGGUCCCGAGAGCCUCCCCAGAGCCGCCGGGCCACGUGCUGGCUGUGUACAGCUCGAGGCUGGUCAUGGUGGAGCCCGUGGAAGCCCAGCCGACCACGCUGGCCGACGCCAUCAUCCUGCUCACCGAGAGCCGCGGAGAGCGGCACGAGGGCCGUGAGGGCAUGACCUGCUACUACCUGACACACGGUUGGGCGGGGCUCAUCGUGGUGGUGGAGAACCGACACCCCAAGGCCUACCUGCACGUGCAGUGUGACUGCACCGACAGCUUCAACGUGGUGUCCACACGCGGCAGCCUGCGUACCCAGGAUAGCGUGCCACCCCUGCACAGGCAGGUCCUGGUGAUCUUGUCCCAGCUAGAGGGCAACGCCGGCUUCUCUAUCACCCACCGCCUGGCACAUCGCAAGGCAGCCCAGGCCUUCCUCAGUGACUGGACAGCCUCCAAGGGGACCCACAGCCCCCCACUCACGCCAGAGGUCGCCGGUCUGCAUGGGCCCCGACCGCUGUGACCACCAUGCCUGGGGCAGGGGCUGUGCACAGACGGACCCCCCACCCCCACACGCACUUUAUGAGGGAGACCCCGACAGAGGACGCUUGAGCCAGAAUCUCAGGACCCCGCCCAGGGAGCUGCCAGCCCAGGGCUCAGCUUCCCAUGGGCCCCCCGCCCCCCUCCUUCCCCUCCCUGAACCCCACAGUCCGCCUGGCCAGGCCUCCUGGCCGCCACGCAGAAUACCUCGAACCAGGCGGGCUGUGAACCAGCCCCGCUCACCUGCCAGCCCCAACACCCGACGGGGGCCGAGGCCAGGCUGCCCCUCCCUGUGGGCUCAGGGUCUCCUGCGGGCUAGGCAGCCAGGAGCUCUGUCCGCAAAACCAAAUCUGGGUGUCAGAGGCCAAGACCCUGGGGUGGGAUCAGGGACCACCCCUCACGGGGCAUAAGGUCAGUUUUCCCCCAGAGCCCGGGUCCCUGUCCCCCACAGGGCAGGCGGGGUCCCUGGAGCCCUGGUGUGGAGCGGCGAGUCCCGGGGCGGUGCCUGUCUCAGAAGAAGGGGCCCUUGGCCAGCCCCCCAGCGACACUAUGCAAAUCCUGGAGUGCCCGCCAGGAUCGAAGCCAUGACUGGGUGCAGGCGGGCGCCAGGCCCGCUGUGGGUGGGCACCAGUUCUCAGCACCGCUCACUGCUGCCGGGCACACUGGGACCAGCAGGCUCCUCAGCCAACCCUGUCCCUCGGCCCGGCCCUGCCAGAGAGGGACCCCAGCACAUCGUGGGCACGGGCAGGGCUCAGCCGCUCCCACCUCCCCACAGAAGCCCAGGAGUGUGUGGACGUCUGAGCCCAGCUUUCUGCGUGCCCUCCUGGCCCCUCACUCCCGGCAGCGGGCCGGCCUCGCCCCCACUCCCCCUCCUACCCCGGCAGGGGCUUCCGGGGCCUUUUCACCUGGAGAAACAUUCCCACUCCCCUUUGGCCUCCCUGUACUCUGAGCUGUGAAUAUUUUUAACCCUGUAAAUACGGCCAGCUCUUGUGACACAGAGACUAUUUUAUCAAUUGUCAGUCCCGUUCCUUUACCAUAGGAUUCUCCACAGUGGCUUCCGACUCAGGCUCCAAUGGACCAAAUAAAAGCGUUUUGUUUUGUAA